GCGCCGAGCUGACCGGGCGACGCCGCGGGAGGUUCUGGAAACGCCGGGAGCUGCGAGUGUCCAGACAUCCUUGUGGAACCAGCGUUGUUUUUCCUUGGCAGCUGCGGAGACCCGUGAUAAUUCGUUAACUAAUUCAACAAACGGGACCCUUCUGUGUGCCAGAAACCGCAAGCAGUUGCUAACCCAGUGGGACAGGCGGAUUGGAAGAGCGGGAAGGUCCUGGCCCAGAGCAGUGUGGUGAGCGCUGUGCUGGAAGGGAAUGCGGGCAGUGGGUACUUGGUAGAGCACUGACUGCCUCCGGCCAGAGGACUUCCCGGAGGAGGUGACCCAUGAGCUGGAGUGGUCAGAGGAAGGCUGGCAAAAGGGCAUCGUGGACAGAGGAACAGCCUAUGUGAGUGGGAGCAGAGACCUUGGCCAAUGCCAUUCCUUAUGGCCUUGUAGUGGAAGCAAGGUGAUGGGGAAGGAACACUGUAGGGGAUAGCUGUCCACGGACGCUGUCUACAAGACCCUGGAGUGAGAUAACGUGCCUGGUACUGUGCCCUGCAUGUGUAAGAUGCCCAGUUGACCUUCGCAGCAGGAGCCUGGAUCAGGGCACUUCCUGCCUCAGGUAUUGCUGGACAGCCCAGACACUUCCCUCUGUGACCAUGAAACUCUGGGUGUCUGCAUUGCUGAUGGCCUGGUUUGGUGUCCUGAGCUGUGUGCAGGCCGAAUUCUUCACCUCUAUUGGGCACAUGACUGACCUGAUUUAUGCAGAGAAAGAGCUGGUGCAGUCUCUGAAAGAGUACAUCCUUGUGGAGGAAGCCAAGCUUUCCAAGAUUAAGAGCUGGGCCAACAAAAUGGAAGCCUUGACUAGCAAGUCAGCUGCUGAUGCUGAGGGCUACCUGGCUCACCCUGUGAAUGCCUACAAACUGGUGAAGCGGCUAAACACAGACUGGCCUGCGCUGGAGGACCUUGUCCUGCAGGACUCAGCUGCAGGUUUUAUCGCCAACCUCUCUGUGCAGCGGCAGUUCUUCCCCACUGAUGAGGACGAGAUAGGAGCUGCCAAAGCCCUGAUGAGACUUCAGGACACAUACAGGCUGGACCCAGGCACAAUUUCCAGAGGGGAACUUCCAGGAACCAAGUACCAGGCAAUGCUGAGUGUGGAUGACUGCUUUGGGAUGGGCCGCUCGGCCUACAAUGAAGGGGACUAUUAUCAUACGGUGUUGUGGAUGGAGCAGGUGCUAAAGCAGCUUGAUGCCGGGGAGGAGGCCACCACAACCAAGUCACAGGUGCUGGACUACCUCAGCUAUGCUGUCUUCCAGUUGGGUGAUCUGCACCGUGCCCUGGAGCUCACCCGCCGCCUGCUCUCCCUUGACCCAAGCCACGAACGAGCUGGAGGGAAUCUGCGGUACUUUGAGCAGUUAUUGGAGGAAGAGAGAGAAAAAACGUUAACAAAUCAGACAGAAGCUGAGCUAGCAACCCCAGAAGGCAUCUAUGAGAGGCCUGUGGACUACCUGCCUGAGAGGGAUGUUUACGAGAGCCUCUGUCGUGGGGAGGGUGUCAAACUGACACCCCGUAGACAGAAGAGGCUUUUCUGUAGGUACCACCAUGGCAACAGGGCCCCACAGCUGCUCAUUGCCCCCUUCAAAGAGGAGGACGAGUGGGACAGCCCGCACAUCGUCAGGUACUACGAUGUCAUGUCUGAUGAGGAAAUCGAGAGGAUCAAGGAGAUCGCAAAACCUAAACUUGCACGAGCCACCGUUCGUGAUCCCAAGACAGGAGUCCUCACUGUCGCCAGCUACCGGGUUUCCAAAAGCUCCUGGCUAGAGGAAGAUGAUGACCCUGUUGUGGCCCGAGUAAAUCGUCGGAUGCAGCAUAUCACAGGGUUAACAGUAAAGACUGCAGAAUUGUUACAGGUUGCAAAUUAUGGAGUGGGAGGACAGUAUGAACCGCACUUCGACUUCUCUAGGCGACCUUUUGACAGCGGCCUCAAAACAGAGGGGAAUAGGUUAGCGACGUUUCUUAACUACAUGAGUGAUGUAGAAGCUGGUGGUGCCACCGUCUUCCCUGAUCUGGGGGCUGCAAUUUGGCCUAAGAAGGGUACAGCUGUGUUCUGGUACAACCUCUUGCGGAGCGGGGAAGGUGACUACCGAACAAGACAUGCUGCCUGCCCUGUGCUUGUGGGCUGCAAGUGGGUCUCCAAUAAGUGGUUCCAUGAACGAGGACAGGAGUUCUUGAGACCUUGUGGAUCAACAGAAGUUGACUGACAUCCUUUUCUGUCCUUCCCCUUCCUGGUCCUUCAGCCCAUGUCAACGUGACAGACACCUUUGUAUGUUCCUUUGUAUGUUCCUAUCAGGCUGAUUUUUGGAGAAAUGAAUGUUUGUCUGGAGCAGAGGGAGACCAUACUAGGGCGACUCCUGUGUGACUGAAGUCCCAGCCCUUCCAUUCAGCCUGUGCCAUCCCUGGCCCCAAGGCUAGGAUCAAAGUGGCUGCAGCAGAGUUAGCUGUCUAGCGCCUAGCAAGGUGCCUUUGUACCUCAGGUGUUUUAGGUGUGAGAUGUUUCAGUGAACCAAAGUUCUGAUACCUUGUUUACAUGUUUGUUUUUAUGGCAUUUCUAUCUAUUGUGGCUUUACCAAAAAAUAAAAUGUCCCUACCAGAAGCCUUAAAGAGCCUUACUUGGAGUAUUUUUAAGACUGGAAGCUUUUACCAGGUUCAUCAUUUCCUAUGCAUCACCUUCAUGCAGGCAGAGUCUGGAUAAUGAAUGCUUUAGCAGCAAAAAAGCAUCUUGGGUCUUGGAUUUCAGACCUGGUUUCAACACUUGUGUUCCCUCUAAGUGUCAGUGUCCUUUUCUGGAAAGUAGGGUAAAUAGUUUCUCUUUGUCUCCCAGAGAACAUAGCACAUGUGUUCAUGAUUGUAAUGCUGUUAUAAUGUGUACUUCAUUUUUAAAUUUUGAGAUAAGAAUUGUUCAUGAUACACAGAUGUAUACUUAAAAAAAUAUGAAGGUGAGCAGGAGCACCUGUGUCAACACCAAGUUAGAAAAGAGAACGUUUUCAAGUCAGUACCUCAGGAGCCCCUUGGGAACCCCUCCUAGAUCACAUCUCCUUCACUGCCCCCAGCACUUUGGAGAUAAAUCAUUGUCUCAUGAUGUGUGGUACUCAUUCCUUUGCUUGUCUUUAUAGUUUUACCAUCUAUGAUUAGAUCCCUAAAUAAGUAGUUAUUCUGUUUUCCCUGAUUUUGAACUUUUACUAAUAGAAUGAGAGUAAAUAUUUUUGGGUAUGUGGCUUCUUUUGUUCAACAUUGUUUUAAGAUUCAUCCGUGUUGCUUGUGUAGCUGUAAUUUGUUUUAAUCUUUAUAGUACAUUCAGUUUUGUUAAUGCUUAUUGUAGGACUGUACCAUAAUACAGGCAGCAUGCUGCUGAUAAACACUGGAAUUGAUUUCAGUCUUUGUAUAUUGUGAAUAAUGCUGUGAUAAACAUUUUUAUACAUGAUUCCUGGUGCACAUAUAAACACAUAUUUCUGUAGGAUAUAUAUCUAGGAGUGGAAAUGUGGAGUCUUAAUGGUGUUCCAACUUUACUAAAUAAUGUAUUCCAAGGUGGUUAUACACAUUCUCACCAGGAGUAAAUGAGAGUUAUUACCCCAAUCUUUUCCAGUAUUUAGUAUUUUCAUACUUUUGAAUUUUAGCUAGCUUGGUACAUGUUACGGACUAAAUGUUUGUGUCCCCCCACCAGAUUCAUAUGUUGAAAUCUUUUUUUUUUUUUUUUUUUUUGAGACGGAGUCUCGCUCUGUCGCCCAGGCUGGAGUGCAGUGGCGGGAUCUCGGCUCACUGCAAGCUCCGCCUCCCGGGUUCACGCCAUUCUCCUGCCUCAGCCUCCCAAGUAGCUGGGACUACAGGCGCCCGCCACUACGCCCGGCUAAUUUUUUGUAUUUUUAGUAGAGACGGGGUUUCACCGUUUUAGCCGGGAUGGUCUCGAUCUCCUGACCUCGUGAUCCGCCCGCCUCGGCCUCCCAAAGUGCUGGGAUUACAGGCGUGAGCCACCGCGCCCGGCCCAUAUGUUGAAAUCUUAACCCCCAAUGUGAUGAUAUUAGGAUGCGGAGCCCUUGGGAGGUCGUAAGCAUGGAGCCCACGUGAGUGGGAUUAGUGCCCUUAUGAAGAGAUCCCAGCCCUCUUUCUGCCAUGCGAACACACAGCAAGAAGAUGCCUGUCUAUGAACCAGGGGGCCCUUACCAGAAACAAACCUACUAGCAUCUUGAUCUCGGACUUUCCAGUUCCCAUAACCAUGAGAAAUAAAUGUUUUUAAUUCAAUGUAUGGUAUUUUAUUAUAGCAGCUCUACCUAAGACAGUACAUGUAUAGUGUCUAUUUGAACAUUACUGAUAAUGUUGAACAACUUUUCAUGUUUAUUAGUUAUUAGGUUUCUUCAAGUGUUCUUAUUCAUACAAAUUUUAAAAUAUGUACACAAGUUCUUUGUUAUAUAUUUUGCAAAUAUCUUCUGUGGCUUGUCUUUUCACUAUUUUAGUUCUGUCUUUUGAUAAACAGGAGCUUUUAAUUUUUAUGUCAAAUCUAUCAAGCUUUUUCUUUUUGAUUUAUGUUUUUUAUGUCUUAUUUGAGAAAUCCUUCUAUACCCCAAGAUCAUGAGGAUGUUUCCUGUGUUCUCUUCUGAAAGCUAUAUAGUCUUUGUCAUUUAGGUUUAUCUUUAUACGUGGUAUGAAGUGUAAAGUUCUACUUUUAAUUUUUUGCAUAUUUUAUUAGGAUAGGAUGGGCUUUUUCUGUAGUAAUAAUCCUUAAAUCUCAGGGGCUUAAUAUAUAAAAUUGUCUCAUGCAAAAAACCACUGGGUCUAGGGCAAUUGCUAUCUACUGCCGUCUAAUCUCCCUCUAGUGGCUUCCAUUGGUAGACCCUAACAGGAAGCCAGCUGAUAAGGGAAUCUGGGAAAUGUAGUUUACAGAGUGGCAGCUACAGUAGAACAGUAGAGACUACAAGGAUGAGCUUGCAGCUGAGAAUAGAAACGUGACUGGCACACUAGGUGGUUUGUUUGUAGGUUUUUUCUUUUCCUGUUUGAGACUUUUUUGGAUUCUUGAAUUUGUACAAUGGUAUCCUUAAUCAAUUGUGGAAAAUUAAAUGAUUUUUUCUUUCA